CCAACACCACGACUGAGAACGGGAUUGUUUAAUAAGAUCACACCACCCCCUGGGGCAACUAAAGACAUCUUGAGAAAAUGUGCCACCUCUCAGGUGCCACCAGAGCGACUGGGGAGACAGGAUAGAAUUUCCAAAACAUGCUCCAUUGGAAAUUGCCUCACCAGUUCUAAGGUGUGAGGAACUACAGUGUCCCCAUAGGCUUGGACUCCAGAGUCCUCGUGGAUUUAGUUGUGGUGGGAUCCGUCGCCGUUUCUGAAAAAGGUAAGACUAGCAGAUGGGAACCCUUGAGUGUGACAGCUCUGCCUGAAGGCGGCUGCGUGCCAGGCUGUUUGUCUUUCAAAAGUCGCCAGUGGUGUCUGCUUUCUGGAUGCGCUUACCUGGUCUCCGAAGCCGCUGCAUUUUUCAGAGGUGAAGAAUUGGCUCAGCCCACCCGCUUCUGGCCCCAGCCCAACAUGUGUACAGCAUUUUCACUUUUCUUAGCAGGAAAAACAAAGUGAGAUAACUCUCUGUUCAGGUGGUGAAAGGUUUUCUCUCUGUUCUUGAGUGAGCUGGAGCUUAAUUUCUUUUCAGUAUGUCAGUAAAUAGUUGGUUUUGGAGGGACUCCAGCAAAUGGAAAAACAGUAGGUUCCAAGCUUUGUUUUUAUUAUGAAGCAGCAGACUCUUGAACAACACGGUGUGUCCGAGACUCCUGAACAACGUGGUGUGUCCGAGACUCCUGAACAACGUGGUGUGUCCGAGACUUCUUCUCAGGCCUGGUGCUUUGCCACGCUGCAUGUGAGGCAGGCUGCUCUCGGUCCACAAGGCCAGGGGGCCCUUGCUAAGAGGGCAGGGUCACCACACCACCUCUUGCUGUCUCCAGCUUCAGGGUGCCCUCUUUUCCCAGCCACCACUGGAGCUGAUGUGGGGACAUUGUUCUUUAUUCUUUGCUUUCAGUGCAUUCCCAGUUUCUGGUGCUUCGUCUGUGUCAUCGGGGCUGGGGACUCAGGAGCGCACUGUUCUGGUAUACCUGCUACACCUGCUGUGUGCCAGGCAGGCACUGGGUGGUCUUUAAGUGCAUGGUGUGUGGGUGGGCCAGACACGAGAGCUGGACCAGGACAGGACGUGACGUGCUCAGUGCUGGACACAAGUCAGGACCGACGGGAGGGGGAAGGGGAGUCUGAGGAGGGACGUGCCAGCCUGGAGGGGGCAUCUCCUCAGUAGCGGCCUCAGGGCUGGCUCCUGCAUGCCGGCCACAGUCCAGGCAGAGGGGACUGAAGGGUCCUCAGGCAGCAGGCCCUUUACUAGGUUGCGGCCCCUUCUCAGCAGCCUUGAGGCCAGAUGAUGGGACUUGGGCUCUUGGUGGUGGGAAAUCAGCAAAGGUCCCCUCUUGGAAAAUAUCAUCAGGUUCAGGGAUGUAUAAAGAAGAAAGUAACACUUCGUAAGUUUCAUCGUUUAGCUAACCCCCUGUGUAAAGUAGUAAAGUAACCAUGUGUCUGCUUAGAAAAUUGAACAGCACAGAAAGCUGCACCAUAAGUCUUCCCUGUUCCUUCCCAGCUGCCCCAUUAGGAGUUCCUAGUGUAGACGUUGUACAUAGUAGCAUGCGUGUGAGACACAGAUAUCUUUUUUUUUUAAGUUCCGGGAUACAUGUGUAGGAUGUGCAGGUUUGUUACAUAGGUAAACGUGUUCCAUGGUGAUUUGCUGCACCUACCAACCCAUCACCUAAGUAUUAAGCCCAGCAUGCAUUAGCUAUUUUACCUGAUGUUCUCCCUCCCACUGCCCCUGCCCUGACAGGCCCCAGUAUGUGUUGUUCCCCUCCCUGUGUCCAUAUGUUCUCAUUGUUCAGCUCCCACUUACGAGUGAGAACAUGCAGUGCUAGGUUUUCUGUUCCUGCGUUCGUUUGCUGAGGAUAAUGUUUUCCAGCUCCAUCCAUGUCCCUGCAAAGGACAUGCUCUCAUUCCUUUUUAUGGCUGCAUAGUAUUCCAUAGUGUAUAUGUACCACAUUUUCUUUAUCCAGCCUAUCGUUGAUGAGCAUUUGGGUUGAUUCCAUGUCAUUGUUAUUGUGAAUAGUGCUACAGUGAACCUACAUGUGCACGUGUCUUUAGAGUAGAAUGAUUUAUAAUCCUUUGGGUAUAUACCCAGUAAUGGGAUUGCUAGGUCAAAUGGUAUUUCUGGUUCUAGGUCCUCUAGAAAUCAGCACACUGUCUUCCAUAAUGGUUGAAUUAAUUUACCUUCCCACCAACAGUGUAAAAGUGUUCCUAUCUCUCCACAGCCUUGCCAGCAUCUGUGGCCAUUCUGACUGGCAUGAGGUGGUGUCUCAUUGUGGUUUUGAUUUGCAUUCCUCUAAUGAUCAGUGAUGUUGAGCUUUUUUCCAUGUUUGUUGGCUGUAUAAAUGUCUUCUUUCGAGGAGUGUCUGUUCAUGCCCUUUGCCCACUUUUUAUUGGGGUUGUUUGGGUUUUUUUCUUGUAAAUUUGUUUCAGUUUCUUACAGACUCUGGAUAUUAGACCUUUGUCAGACAGAUAGUUUGCAAAAUUGUCUCCUAUUUUGUAGGUUCUCUGUUCACUCUGAUGAUAGUUUCUUUUGCCGAGACACAGAUAUGUUAUAGCAGUGGUCCCCAACUUUUUGGCACCAGGGACCGGUUUCAUGGAAGACAAUUUUUCCAUGGACCAGGGAGGGGACGGUUUCAGGAUAAUUUAAGCACAUUACAUUUAUUGUGUACUUUAGUUCUGUUAUUCCUACAUCAUAAUAAAUCACAGAGUAAUUAUACAACUCAUAAUAAAGAAUCAGUGGGAGCCCUCAGCUUGUUUUCCUGCAACUAGACGGUCCCAUCUCAGGGUGAUAAGAGACAGUGACAGAUCAGCAGGCAUUAGAUUCUCAUCAGGAGCACGCAACCUAGAUCCCUGGCAUGCACCAUUCAUACGAGGGUUUGCACGCCUGUGAGAAUCUAAUGCCGCAGCUGAUCGGACAGGAGGCGGAGCUCAGACAGUAAUGAGAGUGAUGGGGAGCGGCUGUAAAUACAGAUGAAGCUUCACUCUCUCACUGCCCACCUCGUGCUGUGUGGCCCGGUUCCUCACAGGCCAUGGACUAGUACUGGUCUGUGGCCCAGGAGUUGGGAACCCCUGUCUUAUAGUUUUUAGGUAUAGAUGUAUAGAUAUCCCUUUUCUGCAUUCACAGAAGGGACGGUGGCACACACAGAGCUCCGUGCCUUGCUGGAGACUGUGUCUUAGAGCCCCUUCCUGUCAGCACUGCGGGCUGGCCUCCUGGGCCCGUGUUGAGGAACUGCACGGUGUUCUCACGUGACUGCACCUCAGUAACUGAAGCCCACCCCCGCCGAUGGAUGCAUACGUUAUGAGUUAUUUCCAGAUUUGGCUUUGGUCUUUUCUCUUACAGACCAUGUUGGAGUGAAGUAUGUUCUGUGGGAUAGUCUAGGUGCACCUUUGGGGCUAUCCAUGGGGGCCAAUGCCUCGGAGGGGAGUUGCUGAACUGAAGGGUGGAUUGUCAGCCUUGAUGUUGCCACCAGAAGGGCCGCUCACUUUCGGCCCUCAACAGUGGUGCCUGGCCUCUUUUCCCGCUUCCUUGUUCCUAGCUGGAGUGAGCCAGCUUUGACUUUGAGCAGUCCGCUAGUGAGCAGUGACUAGCAUCUCCUUUGCCUUUGAUUUGCACCUAAUUAGGAGGCAGUCAAGCAUUUUUCAUGUUUGCGGCUUAUCUGCCUGUCAUUUUCUGUGAACUGUUCAUAUCCUUUGCUAUUUUUCUGUUGAAUUUUCUUUCUCUUGUUUCUCUGCAUGCACAGUUGAAGGUUUUGAAUUGUCAAAGUAGCUUGAUCAGAUGUGAGUCUUAGACACGGCAGCAGUGAUGCGGGUGCUCUGCGGGUGAUGCUGCUGGUGGCACUCGCUGGCCUCAGUUUCUGAAGUGCCUCAGGCUUCUCAUAAGCGGAAUUGUAGCUUCUCCAUGGGGGCCAGAAGGCAUUUGAUGUAUCCUGUCUUCCUGCAUUUUUGUCUCUGAAUAGCUGAUUUGGCUAGAGAGGCUGUUAAACCUCGAUUUCAUCUUAGCUACUCUUUUAGGCUCAGAUAAUCCUUUUGUUGUGCCACUAAUUACAAAUUUGCAAAACGCUUUAGUACUGCUUAAACCGUCCCUCAGGACCUGGUAUCUAGUGGUGAGUAUUCAGUGCUUUUGAAGAAACAAGGCCAUGCCCUCACACACUCCUGACUUCAGAGCAGCGAUUUUCCCUCCGAGGUAAGUUGAUUAAACAUGUUUUGCUUUCAGUGGGAAUUUGUUUUUAGUCUUUUUGAGAACUGCUCUUUUCAUUCUUUUUAAGUAUGAGUCUUGCUAACAUAAAGCUGACAUGAGUGUGAUCUGUUUCCCUUUGUGACAUGCUUGAACGGUCCAGUGUUCACGUCAUUGUAGUUUCACCACCUGACAUUGGCCGUGUUGUUAUUCCUGUUGAAUGCCCAAAAGUCCAUCGUCAGUGUGGGCUGCUUGUGGGCAUUUGGUGGGCAUUUCUGUGAAAAUUUCUAUAGAUUAGCUCGGGAUAUUGGGUUCAAGUUUCUUCUUCCACUGGACCUGAUGGAAAAUCCACUUCUCAGCGAUGCCCCGGACCGCACAGCGAUACUGAUUCUCGGUUGUCUCUUAGGCUGGAGAAUCGGGAAGGGAGAAGGCUACGCCGAUCUGGAAUAUGCCAUGAUGGUAUCCAUGGGCGCCGUCAGCAAGGAGACGCCGGUGGUCACCAUCGUCCACGACUGCCAGGUCGUGGACAUCCCUGAAGAGCUUGUUGAGGAGCACGACAUCACUGUGGACUACAUCCUCACUCCAACCAGAGUCAUCGCCACAGGCUGCAAGCGCCCAAAGCCAAUGGGAAUCACCUGGUUCAAGAUCAGCCUGGAGAUGAUGGAGAAAAUCCCCAUACUGAGGAGCCUCCGCGCCCGAGAGCAGCAGGCUGGGAAGGAUGUCACCCUCCAGGGUGAGCACCAGCACCUUCCGGAACCAGGCUGCCAGCAGACAGUGCCCCUGAGUGUUGGCAGGAGGCCCCCGGACACACCCGGACCAGAAACCAAUUCCAUGGAGGCAGCCCCUGGCUCCCCACCAGGGGAGGGUGCCCCGCUUGCAGCCGAUGUUUACGUUGGGAACCUCCCCGGGGACGCCCGUGUGAGUGACCUGAAGAGAGCCCUGCGGGAACUCGGCUCCGUGCCCCUGCGGCUCACCUGGCAGGGCCCGCGGCGCAGAGCCUUCCUCCAUUACCCGGACUCUGCCGCAGCCCAGCAGGCCGUCUCCUGCUUGCAGGGCCUGCGCCUGGGCACCGACACCCUGAGGGUGGCGCUGGCCAGGCAGCAGAGGGACAAGUGACCUCGUGGACAGCCACGGAGCUCACUGCAGACUCGCCAUCCCCGUCCCCUGCCGCUCCGGUUCCGAUGGCACUCGAGAGGCCUGCGUGGCAAGACGUGUCGGAGCCACCGCCUGAGCUGCUCGGGUCUCAAUUCUUCUCAGAAGUCACCGCUCAGUGAACGCCCAGGCCCUCCUGUGAGUGGGGAAGCCGCCCUGCGGUUCAUCUCACAGCGCGCAGAGACUGCAGCCUCCCAAUCGUGCAGGCUCGGGCCUUGAGUCGGUUUCUGUUUCUCUGGAGGGACAGAGCAGAGGGGCCAGGGACUGAGUGAGUGGCUAAGCAGGGGAGGGUGAUGUGAAGGUGAUCUCGAGUUUGCCAGGGGUGGGCUGAACAGGAGAAGAUGAACAAAGGAUCCGGCUCUCAAAAGGCCCUGGCAGGGACUGGAUGCUGGGUACAGAAGCGCGCCCUUGGGCUUCAGGCUCCUGAGCUGGCAGCACGGCAGGGAGAGCUCCAUCCAUGUCGCAGGAGCCCAGGAAGCUCAGCCCCUGGGUAAAAAGUGCUCACUGCAGCUCAGAUCAGUCCUCAGGUCACAUUUCGGGGAGCCAGCCUCCCCUCUUCCCCUCCCCAGCCCCGCUCCUCCCUCUGUGGACACACUCCGGGCCCUCAGCCAGCUGGCUGCAUGAGGAGCAGCUUUGUGCUGUGGGAGAGACCGGCUCUGGGAGAAUGGGUUUCAUCCCAGCCUACGUCACAUUUGCCCAGUGCCUUAUGUUUUCUGGGUUUUUUUCCUCCAGUUCUGUUUCUAAAAACCAGCUUGAGUUUGGCUGAACUGUCCUUUCUCAACAGAAGCGCUUUUGCAAUUGAUCCCGGGCAACAAGUCAAAAUAAGCUUUUAAGUGGAGAUUUUGUUUUUUUCAAAUGUAUAUGCUUUGGAAAUUUUGAUUUUUUAGCCAGAGGGUUUUACCAAGUGUUCUUUGAAGCACAUUACGAUGCCUCGAGAGGGCGGCCCGUGCACGCGCUUUCAAGAAAAUGUUCUCGGGACACUCGGUCUUCUCUUUGAAAGGACAUUUUCUCAUUGGUUUUGCCGUGAAAAUCCUGUGGAGACUUCGCAAAGAAAACGCAGCCUUACAUUUGCUCAUUAAAGACAGAUUUCCUUCCCAAGUCGCCAUGAAUAAAAUGAGAGAGUAGAAACGUCUGGAAGCGCCACACCUGGCCCUGGGCCCUCGGCCCUCUGUGUCCUUGGCCUUGCCCCCGCCCGCACGGCUGGUCACGUUUGUCAUUGGGCAUUCAGCUCAGCGUCAGAGGCUGACUCAGUCCCCAGUUCAGAGUAGUCACCUGGUUACACUGAACUCCUCACCUUCUUUUCUCUCUUUUUUUAAAAAAUACUUCUUUUUCUGAAAGAUUCUUAUUUUUUUUUUUUUGUUUACCUUUUUCCUGUGGAUUUGCUGCCGUUAGAAUAGCAACUCCAGGAGAAGAGCAAGUGAGUCAGCCCCCCUUCUCCACUCCCUGCCCCACCGGCAGUGGGCACAGCCCUGCAGACAGGAGCAAGGACUUCGGGGAAUAGACCCACUGGGGCCGGGAGAGGGAGAAGCUGGAUUCUGACCCCACCACUGGCACUCCUGUGUCCAGCCAUGCCUGACGCCCACCCCACCCUCAGACGGCGGGAUUAAACCAGGCAGUACAGGGUUACUCGGGGAAGCCAGACUGCUGGGAUUUCCUGUCGCUUUAGCCAGAAUAAUCCAGGUAUAUGGAUAUACAGAUAAUCUGAAAGAGUUUCUCAUUUUUAUAUUUGUGGAACAUCGUGUAAGAAAAACUGAAGAGCAAGUGCCUGAAAUAAAAUCCCCCACAUGUA